AGAGAGGCUGGCGGCAGUGGUGGCUCUCCCGGCUGGGUUGUCAGUCAGUGAGAGGAGGGGGAAGAUGGCUCACCGGGACCCGUUCUGCUAGGAAGAAGGGGAGCAGGUGGUGCUGCUACUCGGGAGGAAGCAGAGCAGCCUCCGUCGCUGUCGCUGAGAGCCUCACGAGUCGAGGUCCUGCAGGUGGAGCUCCGGCAGCCGCCCUGGUUGAAGGUUUAGAACAGAUGUGGAAAAAUGUUUACUUCAGAGAAAGGGGUUGUGGAGGAAUGGUUGUCAGAGUUUAAGACAUUACCAGAAACAUCUUUACCAAAUUAUGCCACAAAUUUGAAAGACAAGAGUUCUUUAGUUUCAUCUCUCUAUAAAGUUAUCCAGGAGCCACAAAGUGAGUUGCUAGAACCUGUCUGUCACCAGCUCUUUGAAUUCUAUCGCAGUGGAGAGGAGCAGUUGCUUCAAUUUACGCUGCAAUUUCUCCCAGAACUAAUUUGGUGCUACCUUGCAGUCUCAGCCAGCAGAAAUGUGCAUAGCAGUGGAUGCAUUGAAGCUCUUCUUCUAGGGGUUUACAAUUUGGAAAUAGUUGACAAACAGGGACAUACCAAAGUAUUGAGUUUUACGAUUCCAUCUUUAUCCAAACCAUCUGUAUACCAUGAACCUUCCAGCAUUGGGUCCAUGGCUCUGACUGAGAGUGCACUAUCCCAGCAUGGUUUGUCAAAAGUGGUAUACAGUGGACCUCAUCCUCAAAGGGAGAUGCUGACAGCACAGAAUCGGUUUGAAGUGUUGACAUUCCUUUUGUUGUGUUACAAUGCUGCCUUAACUUACAUGCCCAGUGUUUCUCUUCAGUCACUGUGUCAAAUUUGUUCAAGAAUCUGUGUUUGUGGAUAUCCUCGACAACAUGUAAGAAAAUAUAAAGGUAUAAGUAGCAGGAUACCAGUUUCUUCAGGAUUCAUGGUGCAAAUGUUAACAGGGAUUUAUUUUGCCUUUUAUAAUGGAGAAUGGGAUCUAGCUCAAAAAGCACUGGAUGAUAUUAUAUACAGAGCCCAGCUAGAAUUAUAUCCAGAGCCAUUGCUGGUUGCUAAUGCAAUAAAGGCUUCAUUGCCUCAUGGUCCCAUGAAAUCUAAUAAGGAAGGUACAAGGUGUAUUCAAGUUGAAAUCACACCAACUUCCUCUCGAAUAUCAAGAAAUGCAGUAACCAGCAUGUCAAUAAGGGGUCAUAGGUGGAAAAGACAUGAGCAACCUGACAACAAUAAUGAUGCUACUGAAUUGGGCAUCCUUGUCAUUCCUGAGAUUAGUGUCACAAAUGUGGCCGGAGAGAGAACCGGGAAUGGGGAAAAAGGCAGAACACUAGGAGAGAUUGAUGCUCAGCAUAUACAGGGUGUGCAGGAAACAGCCACAGAUCCUAGAACUGAGAGCAAAGGCUUGCCAGAGAUCAGGAGGCAAAAAUCUGUAAGAAAAAUGAUGGAGGAUGGAAUAAACUCACCUGGCAGAGUGCAGUUUUAGCAGAGCACUUUAUAACUGCACUCCAAGGAAAUACAGAAUUAACAGGUCAAGAAGAACUGAUGGAGAUAUCUGAAGUUGACGAGGGAUUUUAUUCCAGGGCUGCGUCUAGUACCAGCCAGUCGGGUUUAUCAAACAGUAGUCACAAUUGUAGUAACAAGCCAAGUAUAGGAAAGAACCACAGACGGUCAGGAGGAAGCAAAACUGGAGGAAAAGAAAAAGAAACUACAGGGGAAUCUUGCAAAGAUCACUUUGCUCGAAAACAAACUCAGAGAGCCCAAAGUGAGAAUCUUGAGCUUCUCUCUUUGAAGAGACUUACUUUAACAACCAGCCAAUCCCUACCUAAGCCUAGUAGCCAUGGUUUGGCUAAGACCGCAGCGACUGUAUUUAGUAAAUCCUUUGAACAAGUCAGUGGUGUCACAGUCCCACAUAACCCGUCAUCUGCUGUUGGUUGUGGGGCUGGGACAGAUGCCAAUAGGUUUUCCGCUUGUAGUCUCCAAGAAGAAAAGCUUAUUUACGUUUCAGAAAGAACUGAACUUCCAAUGAAGCAUCAAUCAGGUCAGCAGAGACCUCCUAGUAUUAGCAUUACUCUGUCCACAGAUUAAUUAGUAACAUAUUUUUCUCCCAUAACCUAGUGAACCUGGAAAUACAACUUUGCUUCUUUAUGAAAGUACCCUGGGUCUUUCAUCCGUAUUCCUGACAGGAGCCCUGAUGUCUUAAAUUCUGAAGGCUCCCCUGACUUUAUGAAGGGAAGAUUGUCUAGGUUGCAGUAAGUUGAAAUAUGGUUUUGUUAUUUCUUGAUUAAGAUUUUUUCCCCUUGGUUUGAGUCUUUUUUUUCCCUCCUCUUAUUUGUUAUUGUUGCCCUAAGAUUGUCAGUGACAAUAAAUUUUGACAGGUUGUCUAAUCAAGUUGGUUAUGUCUCAUGUGAGGUUGUAAGGUGGUUUUUCUUGUUUUGGUUUGGUUUGGUUUUUUAAUAGCUCCUAUUUUGAUGGCUGUGUGUUUGGCCUUCAGAGUCAAAGGGAGUCUGCAUGUAUGGGAACUGUUUUAUAGAGAAUGGGGCAGAGGCACAACUCCAGGAAUUCUCUAGCUCCUGGUCAGGAAGCCAAUCUGAAAACAGGCAUGUGGAAACACAAAAAUGAUGUGUAUGAAAAGCACCUGAUGAAAAUAUUUGUAAGCAGAUCAUCUUUAUGAUUAGAACAAUUUGCUCAAAGCCCUGGAAAAUGCCUGGUAACCCAGUGCCUAGAAUAUUAUAUGAUUCCAGGGGAUGGCUAGAGGCAUUUCUGUUGUUAUCUCUGAAACAUUUUUAUAUCAAAAAUCAGAUUGCUGGUAGGUGUGUUGUUUUGAAGUGUUUUAUCUGGAUUUAGCAUGUGAAGAUCCCUUUCAAUUAUUAAGGUAUAAUAGGCUGUAAAGCUGAUUUACCCUACUGCUGGACUUUGGAAAUCCUAGUUAGUUUGGACUCCUAUAAUUCAGAGCAUACGUCAUUGGAAGACUUCCUGGAAAUCAGUGUAAAUCUUGCAACAUAGCUCUCAAGAUACCACUGUAUAAUAUGUAAUUGUUUGUCUGCAAAUGCAUUUUUCAUCUAUAAAAUGUCAUGAAAGAAAAUAAAGGUAGUGAAAUAUGGACAAAGGACAUUUAUAUAUUAACUAAAGUUGUUUAUGUUUGUGUUCUUAAAUUUAAAACACGAAGAAAAAGAAAUGUCUUUCUUGUUAGUGAACAGGCCUGUUUUAAAUAUCUUAGUAUGAUAUCAAAAGAAUAAUCAAUUUAGUUACCUCCCAACUAAAAAGUAAAAAUGAAAAAGACGACAUGGCAGAAGUUGAAACAAACUUGUAUGUAUCUGUAUGUGACCUCUAGAUGGAAAUAAAAGUUUGAUGUUUGCUAGCCGUGGUCCUUUUGGCUAUGGUUGCGGUUCCCCUGUAAAGCAAAUGUACUUAAGUCAUCAUUCAGAGUGAGAGAGAGAAAGCACGGCUGAGGCUGAGUCAGUUGACCGUUGAGGAAGACCUAAGGAGCUGUCCAGUUCUUGGCUCUUUUUCACUGUGACUGCACAGCGGUUUCCUUCUUCAUAGUCCCUUGCUGUAGUCACCAAGAGAGCAUGCUAGUGUUUUCCUCUUGUUCCUGCUUAUGCAGAGCUCAGAUAUAUGAAAAAUUUGUAUGCUUUGAAGGCUGCCAAAGCAUUUAUACUCUGGACAUAGUUUUAACUGCAACUGCUUUGGCUACCAGUUUAAACCGAGUUCUUCAAAAAGCAUGAACUCGUUUUCAUUCAUUAGCCCUGUUUACAAUGUGGAUUUUGACAUAAAUGAAUUUGAUUUUCUUUUAGCUCCAGUAACAGAAUGGAAUAAGAUCUAUUGCCAUAAAUUGUAGUUAAGAACUGUAAGGCAAUCGGGCAGUGAAACUUGAUAUUGUAUUAACUUAAUAGGAACCCUGUGUACAAUUUAAAAUAUUUGUAAAAUAUCACUGUGAAUUUACAGAUGUCUUUUUGUCAUUCUUUAACAAUGAAUUUCCCCUGUGCAUAGUUAUUAAUAGUAUUGGUAUUAUUAAAAACUAAUUUGGCAUUUUAAGAUUGGCAUUUUAAGCAAGUUGAGGUGCUUAGGAAACAUUGUAGAAUAAGUUUGGGGAAAUGUUAGCUGACAGAGCUGAGAGAUCAGAUUUUCAUGUUCUAUCACUGUAAUGGAACCUCAUUUAGACCUCUCUAGACCUUUGCUAGCUGUGUGGUCUGAGGACCAGUAAGUAGGAUUGGCAUUAUCUGGUAUCUUGUUAAAAAUGCAGAAUUUCAUGCCACUCUAGGUCUACUAAAUCAGAAUUUGCAUUCUUAACAAGGUUCCCAAGUGAUUUUUAUGAGAAGAAAGUAUCAGAGUGCAAACAAAUUACUCGUCUAAUAUGUAGAAUUCCCAGUGGUCUCACAGCCCUAGAUCAAAUGUGUCAGACACUAGAUCAUUAUAAUCUUCAUUGGUUUUGACAGCUAAUUAAUUAGUUUAAUAAUAUUGACAUAUGGCUUCUUAAGUAUUUGAAUUCUAGAUUGCUAAUGAUCCUUAUUUUUGCAGUAAAAAAGUAACACUUUAUAUUUUUCUUGUUAACUAUAAAUGGAAUCAGAGCUGUAAAUGCCUGAAAUUUUAAGUGUGAAAAGGGGUGCCACCCUUUUAUAUACUGCACAACAAAUUUGCAUUUGUAUAUUCUUUUUAAAAAAUCUCUGAAGACUUGCUCAGUGAAAUGGUUCUGAUUUUUUGCUUCAAAUGAUUUGCACUAAUUGAUUUUCUGGAGAGCGGAGUUACGUUAACAACAAAAUUCUUUUAUAGUUCCUUUGAUACUAUUUCAAAUAAGGAUUACACAUUGAAAGUUUUUAUAGAAAUUAUGAAAAUUGGAUAAUCUUAACUAUGGUAACCAUUACUAUUAUCCAUACUACUUUCUCCCCACUGAACUUUCAAAUUUGAAAAUUGGGGUAGCUUUUGUAGGUCACUUUCUUAUAAAGAUGCUGAUGGUCACAGAUCUCCUAAGUAUCCAGAAUAAUAUUUUUAUCAUGAGAAGGAUUCCACACAAAAUUGGGGUCUUGCACCCCAUAUUUCAGAGGAUCUGAACAGAAAUUGUGGCUUCAUUGCACAUUUUAAAUCUCUAUAGAUUCUUGAAAUCACCCAACCUCUCACAUUUGAAAACCCAACGGCCUGGAGUAUUCUGGUGGCACUGGAGCCAGCACUAGCUUUUUGGAAUCCAAGUGGGGAGAGAAACAAAAAUAGACUUUUCAAGGGACUGUCCCAGACUACCCAGGGCAAAUGUCUUCCCUUCCCUUCCUGAAGCCACAGGAAAGCACCCUGGAGUCCUUUGUAUACCACUAUGGAAAUUUUUAAGGCAAGCUCUCAAGACUUGAAGAGUUGGAAUUCUCGGCAUUUAAAUGAUGCCUGAAGUUUGUUUUGAAAAAGCAAUAUUUCAUUGCUCUUUUCAAUUGUGAAGCAACUGCUCAGCAAAUAUUACUCAUUUUUUUAAAAAGUUGAAUUAAAGGGAAAUAUAUUUUUAAAACCAAAAUAGAUCAAAAUGAUCCCAGUUUUAAGGGAUUUUGCCUAUUUUGGAAGAAUAAAACUAAAAUGUUAAAACUGUUGAAUUACAGAGAACAGAUGUACUCUGAGACAUAAUUUUAAACAAAUAUUUAAAAUAAGGCAGGUUAACAUUUGCGUUUAGGCACAAUAAAUCUGUAUUAAAGGGAAGCACAUCAAGGAAAUAUAUACAUGUUGAAUAAUGUAACUGAAAAAUAUUUUUUAAAAACCACUUAAAAAGAAAAAUAAUUUGAUGGGUACUUUAAGCAUUGUAGAUAGAAAUUAAUGUAUAAUAGUGUCCUCCCAGUCUUUGUAUGAAAAAUUAAAACUCUCUAGUCCUUUAAUGAGCAUGAAUUUAUACUUCUACAUUUGUUGCUUAGUAAAAUUAUACUCAGUACUUUGAGUUAUUCAGAUUUAUGUUUAAUAUUGUUAAAUUCUUCAUCAGAGAGCAUAAAUAUAUUGUCUUCUAUACUUUGUAACUUGUGCAUAUCUAAAGAAACUAACAACGAACAUUUUGGGAGAUGUUUUUGUGUUUUUUUAUAGUAGAGUUUUAGAGUACAUUUGUCUUAAUAGGAAGUUUUUACCAUAAACCCAAGAUUUUAUUUCACGUAUUGUUGCUUUCUCUUAUAUGGAACUUAUUGUGUACCUCUUACCUUUAUUUCUAAUCAUUUAGUGAUACUAAUCUUUUCAUAGUAAAUAUAUUUGUUUCUAAUUGUAUUCCUAGAGUUUACAUUCCUAAAGAAUAAACGACGACUUUGGCUAUUUUUGUGUGUUCCCUACCUUCUUAAGGCUAUGGAAAUAAACUGGAGUUUAGUUUUUUGAAUUUUUGUAUAUUUGUGUAAAUGUUCUCCAUAUGUAGUACUUUAUACAACAAGUGUUGCCUCUUGUUUUAUUGAAAUAAAAACUGAAAAAAAUAUUUUUUCCAGAUCAGUUUACUCAUUUAAAAAAUUAUUAUAAAAAUUUGCAGAAGUUUUGAUAUGAAGGAAGAGAAUAAAGGAGGAAGACUUAGGUAAGUUGAGCCAUUGAGAGCUUUUGGGGGUAAGUGAUAAGACAAUGACCUCAUUCCUGGCUUUGUGCUUUACAUGUCAUAGGGCUGAGGAGUAUGACAGGUCCACUCGUAUUCAUCCAAAGAUGAAGAUGAGCUCUAUGGGCCAUGCACCAGUGGCGGAUUAUUUGUCAUAUCAGAAGCACAGGCAAAUUUAGGUAACAUCACUUUGUCCUUCUAACUUUAGAAUCUUUAUUGCCAUGUGUGGUGAGUAGUAGUCCCAACUACUCAGGAGGUUCACUCGAGCCCAGGAAUUUGAGACCAGCCUGGGCAAUAUAACGAGAUCUUAUCUCUUAAAAAAAAAAAAAAAGCAAAAGAAGAAGAAAGAGUCUAUAUCUCUUGAGUACAGAGAUUAUAUGCCCCUAGUACCUAGAUAGGACUUUGUGCGUGGUAGGUAUCUAGACAUUUAUGAGACAAUAAAUGAGUUAGGUUGAUGUUAGCUUUGGAAAAGAAUCAAGGAUAAGUCUUCAGUGUUUUCUUUAACAGUACAAUUUUAGAAUUUUGUUUGUUGGCUUUAGGAAAUCUCAGUGGCAUUACAUGAAUUGCAUUAUAGCAUGUACUUAGAAAAAAGAACUUAUGGCUGGGUGCGGUGGCUCACACCUGUAAUCCCAGCCUUUUGGGAGGCCGAGGUGGGUGGAUCACCUGAAGUCAGGAGUUCAAGACCAGCCUGACCAACAUGGCGAAACCCCAUCUCUACUAAAAAUACAAAAAUUAGCCAGGCAUAGUGGCGGGCACCUGUAGUCCCAGCUACUCAGGAGGCUGAGGCAGGAGAAUCACUUGAAUCUGGGAGGCGGAGGCUGCAGUGAGCCGAGAUCAUGCCACUGUACUCCAGCCUGGGCAACAGAGUGAGACUCUAUCUCAAAAAAAAAAAAAAAAAAAAAAAAAAAAAAAAACAGAACCUAUUAACCUAUUAGACACUUGAAAAAAUUCCUGGCUUGUAGUUGAUUAUAUGUUUGGUUAAUUCCAUUUCAUCUAAGGAACUAAGUAAUUUAGGAAAUGUGUUCUUAACUACUCUUAGAAGGGUACUUGUAGAGAACCAGAGUGGUGAUUUUGUAAGCAGUAUUUUGUCCUAUACAAUAUGCACUCUUCCAGUAACUCCAGUAGUCCACAUAGCUGACUCACCUCCUACAACCCGACUUUGUUAAUAUCAAGAUAACUGUUUUAUAAUUGUAGAGAAAGAUUUUUUACAACCAGUUGUAGUUAUUAUUUUCUUUGCAUUAUGUUAUUGUGAUAGUAGUGGUAGCUAAUAUGUGUAAUUAAAAUGAUCAUCUUAUCCUCAAAAUCAUCCUAUAAAGUGCAUAGAAUCCCCAUUUUACAGAAGAGGAAACUGAAGCUCUCAAUAGGGUAGAGGACUUGGCUAAGGUCACCUAGCUGCUGAGUGGCAAAACUCAGCCUUGAACACAGGUCUUAGGACUCUCACUUUAUAUAGCUUGGUAAAAGAAGAUACUAAUUAAAUCCUACCUAAUAGAGAUGUAUUUAAAAUUCACUCACCCCAUCUGUCUUACAGGUAAUAGUUUUAAGGUAAGAUAAAAUCAAAGUGUUCUAAAAGUAAAUCAUAAUACAUUUUACAGAAUUAGAGAUAAUUGUGUUUUAGUGGUCAAACAAUGCUCGUUAUUCUGUUAGUAAAAGCAUGGUAAAAUGCAAAUUAAAAUAAGAUUUCUCUUUUUUUUUCCUGUCAGAUUGAUAAAGAUGAAAAAGAUUGGUUCUAGUAUUGACAUUGGUAUGGGGAAAUCAUUAGUCACUGAGAUGAUUAGCAGGACUGUAGAUUGGUACAAAUGAAUUGGUGGGCAGUUCAACAGGAUCUAUCAGACUUUAAAGUGUAUCUCAUACCCUCUGAAACAGCCAUCCUACUCUUCUAUAUUUAUUCCAUUCUCUGUAUUCUACUGAAAAUUUAGCACAAAUAUAUAAACAUAAGCAUGCAAGGUAUUCAUUGCAGUAUUGCUUGUAAUAGCAAAAACAAGCCAGCAAAUCUAAAUGUCUGUUAAUAGAGGAAUAGAUAAAUUAUGGUACGUACAUAUAGUGGAAUAUAAUGUAGCCAUUAAAAAGAAUGCAGAUCUGUAUGUGAUGAUUUACAUUGAUUAUUCAGUGUAUGAUCCCACUUGCAUUAUAAAUGUGUGCAGUAGUUAAAUAUGAGUGUGUGUAUAUGUAUAAUACACACUUACGUUUGCUAGUAUGGGGGAGGAGAGCAUUGUUUCUCAAAGUGUGGUCUAAAGACAGCCUGCAUUAGGAAAUUUUUUUUUUAAAUGGGGAUUCCUGGGCAUUGUGCUAAUUUCCCUGAAUCAGAAUCACUGUGAGUGAAGCAUGGAAACCUGUAUUUCUAACGGGUUCCUCAGUUGAUGGCUUAUACAAAUGUAAAAUAUGGUCUAGUAGCUGUCAGCAAUGAAUUGGAUAUCUGGUAGUGGAUUGUAGUUAGAAAGGGCAAACUUCUUGAAGAGAUCUUGUAUUUUAAAUGAGGCCUACCUAAAAUAAAGCCAGUUGAGUAACGUUAUCAGCAUAGACCUGUUAAUGAAGGUGAAUUGGCCUGACAUAGAAAAAUGAUUCUACCAUACAGCACUACACACCAACUAAAUGAGCAAGCCUUUUAAAAAAUCCUUGUUGAACUUCCCAAAUAUCAGAUGACCUGUUAAUAAAGCACAAGUAAAUAAUAGGACUUACUGUGGUAAGAGAAAGUGCCACCUUGAUUUGGUUGUGUGUCAGAACCAGAAAGUAAGAUUAUUUGUAGGGCUUUGGGAUCUAUGCUCAAAUGGUUUAAGGUAUGUCUGUCAAGGCAGGGAACUGAUUGGGAUUAGCAAAGUUGAUAGUUCAGAAUUAGUGGACACAGCAAGCAGGGUUCUUGAAGAUUCCUGAAAAGUCAACUGUUGUUUGAGAAACAAGCUGUUUGCCCAGGUGAGCAGGGCUUCACCUGUAGGAAUUGUCUUCAACCUUAGGAAUUUCCUCUACAAACAACAACAACAAAAAAAUAGGGAUUGUUCUUGUUUUUAUUUGCUUUGUUUUGUUUGUAAUCUUAUCUUUCCUGGGCAAAGAUUUCCUGGAAUAAACAACUAAGUUAUGUUGACAUACAUGGGCUACAGUCUUAUCCAAGCUGUAUUGACACUGAUGGAUUCAGUUUGUUUUUCUUAGCUCUCUCUAUUCAAAGAUUAUAAGUCAAUAUUAUGUAUAUAGCAAUUGACAGGUCAUAAGUACGGCAUGCUAACUGAUCGUACCACUGGAGCUCCAACAAUUGAUGUAUCUUUGGUGACUUCUUAGUGUUCUGCUGAAGAUCGCAAAGAUUUCUGUAGCUUCUUGACCUCUAUAACACUUGGUUCACACUUGUUAAGUGUUCUAAUAUAAUCCACAUCACAUUGUGCUGUGACUUAUCUUUCUCAUAUUUGUCUCCCUCACUAGACCACAGCCCUGUGGGAAUAUAAUAUAACUAAUACAUAAUGGUGAAUAAAGAUUUGUUUUACUAGAUAGAAUAUAAAUCGAAUCCAGGAAAUCAGUGGCAGCAUAGGAGAGACUGUGUUGCUUCUCUUCUAUUCAAUAGAAGUCUUUGAAACUCCUUUUAUUCUCUAAUAUUCUUCAUGGAGAUGAAAAUGAAGGUUGUAAAGCUUUACUCUGAUUAUUUUAAGCAUGCCUGCAUAAAAAUGUUUUGAGAAGUAAAUUAUGCAUCAUGUUUCUCUUUAGUUAGACUAUGAAUGGUGUGAAGAAUUUUCUGGGCUAAUGUUUGACAUUUAUUAUUCACUCCUGUAGAUUUGUGGUGAAUAUGAAUGGUAUCUGGACUAAUCAGAAAACAACGUAGGAAAGGCCUAACUUCAACACUGAAUUCUUGCUCCUUGUCUCACUUGCUUCCUUUUGUAGAAACUACAAGUAUAUUUAACUUUUGUAUCCUAGAUCCACUACGGCCUACUGAAAGCCUAUCAUGCAUUUAUCUUUAAACUUUUACUCUCUUCAUUUAGCCAACAUAUUUCUACUUCUAUGUUGCCUGCUGUGCUGUGUAAUUUUCUACAAACAUUUUCACCUCCAAAUCCCUUGAAAUGAAACCCUCUGGAAGAGCAUCACCACUUUUUCUUCCUCUAUUCUAAUUCCCCUCUAGUUUCCCCUCUAGUUUAAGACUUUUGUUUCAAUAUUUAUUCUUUCCUUAAGCCUUUAAAUUCAUUUAUAUCCACCAAGUUGAAUUUGAUGAGACAGGACAUGUUUGAAAGAAGGACAAACCAAACAAGCAAGCAAACCCAUGAAUACUCGUACAAUAGGACAUAAUAUACAUUUCCCAGUUCCCUGAAGGGGUAAAAUUGAGACUGGUUAUACAAGCAGUAUUGCACAGCAUGCUGAUACUAGCUAGACAUAGCCUACAGUGUUUCAGCUUCACUCAAAGAUGGUUCUGGAGGACAGUGAGGAAAUGAACUUUUUCCAGCGAGAAUAAAUAUGAGCAGUAUUUCUAGUCUGCUUUGCACCGAAAGUGAGCCAUCCCAAGAUACAGAUCUACACCAUUUAUACCUGGCCAGGUGGUUGGAAACACAGACGUAAUAAGAUUGGAGGAUGAGUGACAAAAAUUGGGAGCUAAACAUAUUGGACUUCUUAAAAUAGGCUCAGAUUGCAAGAAUAAUUGUUUCCUACAGACAUAUUAAACAAAGGCCCUGUGGUGAAGGAGGUGCUAAAUAAUCAGAUGGUCAAGAUGACUUUGAGGAUAUCAGUAAAUCUCUUUGGUAUUCCAGCCUUUGUUCAAACAGUUUAUGGGCAAAGCGGCUAUACUGGAAGGAUAGGGCUACACAGGAACUUCAACAAUACAGGCCUCCUUUCAUCAAGGCUGUCCUUAUUACUGCCAGGAGCCGAACUGGCCAGCAGCAGUGACCAUCCUAAGAUACAACAUCUGAGGGUGACCAGAUAGUUAGUGGCAGAUUGAUUAUAUCAAAUAUUUUCUUUCAUGGAGAGACAACUAUUUGUCCUCAUGGAAUAGAGCCUUACUCUGGAUCUGGCUUUAAGUUUGCCUUCCCUAAGCACCAUGCUUGUGUGUGCAAUAAUAAGCUUCCUGUUCACCAUUAUGAUUUUCCCCAAAAUAUUGCUUCUAAGAAACUUAUUUUACAAUGUAAUCAGUGAGGUAGAGGUAGAAUUACACUUUCAGUCAUGGGAAACUAGGUAAUUAACAUCAAAAUUCCCAUUGGCAACUAGAUAAUCCAGCAAAACUCUUCAAAACAUGAAAAUCUAGGCCAGGCGCAGUGGCUUAUGCCUAUAAUCCCAGCACUUUGGGAAGCCGAGGUGGGUGGAUCACCUAAAGUCAGAAGUUCAAGACCAGCCUGGCCAACAUGGUGAAAGCCCGUCUCUACUAAAAAUACAAAAAAAAUUAGCCAGGUCUGGUAGCACAUGCCUGUAAUCCCAGCUACUCAGGAGGCUGUGGCAGGAGAAUCGCUUGAACCUGAGAAGCGGAGGUUGAGGUGAGCCGAGAUAGCACCACUGCACUCCAGCCUGGGCAACAGAGGAAGACUCUGUCUCUAAAUAAAUAAACAUGAAAAUCUAGAGAGGCAAGCAUUGGCACAACUUCUUUCCUGGAGGUAUUGGCUGAUUCUAGAAGCAUUUAAGGGGAUAAGCAGUGCUUCUUACUGCUCCAGGAUAUUAGGAGGACAAAAACUGAAUGCCAGUGCCUGCCAAGUCAUAAAAGAGGGCUUAGGAAAUUCCCAUGCUUUGGGCUGGGACCCAAAAAAGCUCCACCAUAGGAGUAAGAGUGAAUUGGAAGUGCAUCAACUCUCCCCCAUACACAGGGAAUUCAGCACGGAUUCAAACCAUCCCAAUUCCUGAAAUCAGAUUAAAAAUGAUCCCCUAAGUGCUUGGUAAUAAACAAAUCCUCUGUGGAGGUGGAAAAAAAACCCCAUCAUCUUAAGCCUCAAGUUCUACAAUUUUUCAAAUACAGUCUUCACAAGAGAAAAGAAAAAUAACCAGACACUUCUAUAGCAGAGCAACACUCAUUGAGAACAACAAGCAGCUUUGGGUAAAAUUGCUUAAAACCUCUGUUUGAAGCCAUUGAAGAACUUUCAGCUAAACAGGACUCUAGAAGACAAAACGCCAGAGAGAAGGUGUGCAGAAAAGAGUUAACAUAAGAGGCUGAGAUGCUAUCCUUAGCCCUGAUUUUAAAGCUGGGCUUUGGCUAGUGUCUGGGAACUUGGAUUACCGGAAUGUUCCCACCAUUCCCUAACUGAUAAGGGGGUUUACUCUUUGUAAACUAUAUAAACAACAUGGUUUAUGCUGAAUUCCCGCUUUGCUUCUAGGAGUCUGGAAUUAUGAUUUGUGCUGGGCAGAGGGUGCCUCUAUCACUAACUUCCAAUACAAACUUUGGGCAGUAAGACUCUAACGAGCAUCCCUGGCAGACAACAUUUCACACCUGUUGUCACAAUUCAGUACUGAAGUAAUUAACCACAGCCUGUGUGAUUCCACAGGCAAAGGAUUCUUGGAAUCUUGUGUCAGGUUUCCUCUGGACUUCACCCCAUGUCCUUUUCCCCUUUGCUGAUUUGCUUUGUAGUACUUUUCUCUAAUAAAUCAUAGCCAUGAGUAUGACUAUAUGCUGAGCCUUGUGAGUGCUUCUGUUGAAUCACUGAACCUGGGGUGCUGGCGUGGUCUUGGGGACUCCCAAUACAAAAGUAUUUUAACCAGAGAAGUGAGCAGACAUUCUGCAGCUACUUCUUCCAUUAUGGAAUUUGCCAAAUCUGGGUAAAAGGCCCAAGAAGAGAGUUACUGUUAAGAAUCAGAGAAGCAAACAAGUUAUGGAAACCACACAGGACUGGAGAAACAAAAAGAACAGGGCCUUUAAACCAAUCGCACUUGGGAGAGCAGAGAUCCUAGUAAGACAGGAAGUUCAGAGAAGUGAGCCUGGCACUUUCCUUGUUUUCCUCUUGAGUAUUUGCUGAAUUCUUGGAUUGCUCAGAGAGGGAAAAAAAAAAAAAAAAAAAAAAAA